GUCGAGAAGCAGCUACCCAAGCUCCAGGAGCUUCCGGUAUGUGUUUUCCCUCUGUUCUCGAUUACCUUGGCAACGGCUGAGGCGGGAGACCGGUGGUCUGCACCGUCCUGGAGGGAGAUAUGAGUGGCUGGACUCUCAGCCAGCCACUGGGAUGUGUUCGGGCUUUGGACCUUGAGGCCGGAGAGAGCUCCCGAGAGGAGGCGGCGCCACGUUCGUUCUUCUGAGGGGACGGUAGAUUUGGGGGUUUUCCUCUAGGAUUCUCGCGCCGUUUCCUCUGAAGAAACAGGACCAGAGAGGGAAGGUGACCUGAAAGUCACAGAAUAAUUUUUUAGAGCUGAACAAGAAUCCAAGCCUGCAACUGCAGAGACGAGAGAUCUUUCUGCUGUCUAUACUCUUGGAAAGCACAUCCUAAGAUCUUUGCAGAUUAUCCUGUGGAAGGAAAAUGCCUAAAGUCAAAAGAAGCCGGAAAGCACCCCCAGAUGGCUGGGAGUUGAUUGAGCCAACACUGGAUGAAUUAGAUCAAAAGAUGAGAGAAGCUGAAACAGAACCGCAUGAGGGAAAGAGGAAAGUGGAAUCUCUGUGGCCCAUCUUCAGGAUCCACCACCAGAAAACCCGCUACAUCUUCGACCUCUUUUACAAGCGGAAAGCCAUCAGCAGAGAACUCUAUGAAUAUUGUAUUAAAGAAGGCUAUGCAGACAAAAACCUGAUUGCAAAAUGGAAAAAGCAAGGAUAUGAGAACUUGUGCUGCCUGCGGUGCAUUCAGACACGGGACACCAACUUCGGGACGAACUGCAUCUGCCGCGUGCCCAAAAGCAAGCUGGAAGUGGUAAUGUCUGACACUCAAGCUUGGUGUUGUUUUCAGCUCAAAAUUCUGCCUUAGUCGACUGCAAGGGAUCUUAUGUUAUUUGGUUGGGCUGGAAUGUCGUUUUGUCCCUGGAUGUCCUGCUGGCUCUCCCUCGUGGGAGUGGGUCCCUGUAUUCAGGAAUCCAUGUGAGGCAGCGUGUGGCUGUGUGUUUGUUAGGUCUGGGGUCAAUCUCAACUCCACUUUUGGGCAAAUUACUGAACCCCUUUCCUCACUUAGGAAAUGGUGGUGGGGAGCCCUAAUCCCAAGGUGGUGGCAGGGUGACAUCAGGGAAGGACAACCAGUGAGUUCCUGUCCCUUUCAGUCCUCACAGUGAUACUUUAACAUUACCAUCACUAUCUUUCCCGCCCCCCCAAGACGGAGUCUUGCUUUGUCGCCCAGGCUGGAGUGCAGUGAUGCCAUCUUGGCUCACUGCAACCUCCACCUCCCGGGUUCAAGCGGUUCUCCUGCCUCAUCCUCCUGAGUAGCUGGGACUACAGGCAUGCACCACCACGCCUGGCUAAUUUUGUAUUUUUAGUAGAGACGGGGUUUCUCAAUGUUGCUCAGGCUGGUCUCGAACUCCCGACCUCAGGUGAUCCACCCGCCUCAGCCUCCCAAAGUGCCGGGAUUACAGGCAUGAGCUACUGCGCCCAGCCCACUGUGUUUCUUCUUUCAGAACUUUCUGUUCCAAGUACCACUCCUAGGCCAGGCG